AAAGUGCUGGGAUUACAGGUGUGAGCCACCGCACUUGGCUAAGAACAAGUGUUUUAACAGAAAAUACUCUGUUUAGGAAACUACAAGGGUUUUAGGACCCAUGAACCAAGAACCAUGGGCAUGGAUAAAGACCAAAAUACAUAUUUCUUAUUACAUCACAAUAUCAGAGAGGUAUAGACUCAGGAUUGGUUGGUUUGCAUAUGUAAGCUGUGCUCAUUGGAAAACUGUGAUUAUCUUUAGGAAUUAGCCCUGAGAGGAGCAGCCUCUCCCUGUUUUUGGUAAGGUCCCCAAAUGCCAGAGCAUCAAGAAUACAGAAAAUAAGAAAAUAUAGUUAAUAUAAUUGGCCUCUUGAUGAACGAGUGCCAAAUAGACUAAUAGAGAAUCUAAGGAAAUGCAGUUAGAACACAGAGGCUAUCUCUGCUUUCCCAGCACGCUGCCUCACCAAGAAAGAAUCCAGAGAAGGACUGGUGGACUUGGAAUGUUAAGUCAUGGCCCAUUUGAUGAUGUUCAGGGAUGUGGCUGUAGAUUUCUCUCAGGAGGAGUGGGAGUGCCUGGACCUGGAACAGAGGGAUUUAUAUAGAGAUGUGAUGUUGGAGAACUACAGCAACAUGGUCUCACUGGGUUUUUGCAUUUAUCAGCCAGAAGCGUUCUCUUUAUUGGAGAAAGGGAAAGAGCCCUGGAAGAUUUUGAGGGAUGAGACAAGAGGACCUUGCCCAGACAUGCAGUCGAGGUGUCAGACCAAGAAGUUAUUACCAAAAAAUGGCAUUUUUGAGAGAGAAAUAGCCCAAUUGGAAAUAAUGAGAAUUUGUAAAAACCACAGCCUUGACUGUUUAUGUUUUAGAGGUGACUGGGAAGGCAACACUCAGUUUCAAACACUUCAAGAUAAUCAAGAGGAAUGCUUCAAGCAGGUGAUACGCACCUGUGAAAAAAGGCCCACUUUUAACCAGCAUACAGUGUUUAAUCUACACCAGAGACUUAAUACAGGAGACAAACUGAAUGAAUUUAAAGAACUGGGGAAAGCCUUUAUUUCUGGUUCAGAUCAUACUCAACAUCAGUUAAUUCACACAAGUGAGAAAUUCUGUGGAGAUAAAGAAUGUGGGAAUACCUUUCUUCCUGAUUCAGAAGUUAUUCAAUAUCAGACAGUUCACACUGUUAAGAAAACAUAUGAAUGUAAAGAAUGUGGGAAGUCUUUUAGUUUACGUUCGAGUCUUACUGGUCAUAAGAGAAUUCAUACCGGUGAGAAACCUUUUAAAUGUAAGGAUUGUGGGAAAGCCUUUAGAUUUCAUUCACAACUUAGUGUCCAUAAGCGAAUUCAUACUGGUGAGAAAUCUUAUGAAUGUAAGGAAUGUGGGAAGGCCUUUAGUUGUGGCUCAGAUCUUACUCGACAUCAGAGAAUUCAUACUGGUGAAAAACCCUAUGAAUGUAAUGAAUGUAGAAAGGCCUUUAGUCAGCGAUCACAUCUUAUUAAACAUCAGAGAAUUCACACUGGUGAAAAACCUUAUGAAUGUAAGGAGUGUGGGAAAGCUUUUACUCGUGGAUCACACCUAACUCAGCAUCAGAGAAUUCAUACUGGUGAGAAAUCUCAUGAGUGUAAGGAAUGUGGAAAAGCCUUUAUUCGUGGUUCAAAUCUUGCUCAACAUCAGAAUGUUCAUGUUGGUAGGAAACCUUAUAAAUGUGAGAAAUGUGGGAAAGCCUAUAUUUGGAGCUCACACCUUGCUCGACAUCAGCGAAUUCAUACUGGCAGGAAACCUUAUGAAUGUAAGCAAUGCGGGAAGACUUUUACUUGGGCUUCGUAUCUUGCUCAACAUGAGAAAAUUCACAAUGAGAGGAAAUCCUAUGAAUGUAAGGAAUGUGGAAAGACCUUUCUUCAUGGCUCAGAGUUUAAUCGACAUCAGAAAAUUCAUACUGGUGAGAGAAACUAUGAAUGUAAGGAAUGUGGAAAGACCUUUUUUCGUGGUUCAGAACUUAAUCGACACCAGAAAAUUCAUACUGGAAAGAGGCCAUAUGAAUGUGAAGAAUGUGGAAAAGCCUUUCUCUGGGGUUCACAACUUACUCGACAUCAGAGAAUGCAUACUGGUGAGGAACCUUACGUAUGUAAAGAAUGUGGGAAAUCUUUUAUCUGGGGUUCACAGCUUACACGACAUAAGAAAAUUCAUACUGAUGCAGAACCUUAUGGAUGCAAGAAAAGUAGCCACAUCUUUAGUCACCAUUCAUAUUUUACUGAACAAAAAAUUCAUAAUAGUGCAAAUCUCUGUGAAUGGACAGACUAUGGGAACACCUUUAGUCAUGAGUCAAACUUUGCUCAACACCAGAAUAUUUACACUUUUGAGAAAUCCUAUGAAUUUAAAGAUUUUGAGAAAGCAUUUUCUUCAAGCUCUCACUUCAUUUCACUCUUGUGAAAUAUUAUAUAAAAGUGUAGGAAGGGCUUUAUUCAUGACUCAUUAAUUGAUGUCAUUUAUUUUUUUCUCUUGAGGAACACCACAAAUGUAAGUAAUAUUGGAAGGCAUUUUAACAGAGCACACAUCCAGCAGCAGCAGCAGCAGCAGCAGCAGAGAAUUCAUCAUGCAAUCAAUAUAGGAAAGAAAUUACUGAUCAGUUAUCAAUUGCAGAAUAUCAGGGUAAAAUUUUAUGAGAUAGCAUGAAUUCUUUUUGAAUCAUUCUCAAAACAUUCUCAUCAGAGAUGUUGCAUAAAGAAUUUAUAUAUAAUUUGGCCAAGCAUGGUGGCUCACACCUGUUAUCCUAGCACUUUGGGAAACAGAGGUGGGUGGAUCACCUGAGGUCAGGGGUUCGAGACCAGCCUGACCAACAUGGUGAAACCCUGUCUCUACUAAAUAUACAAAAAUUAGCCGGGCGUGGUAGCACACGCCUGUAGUCCCAGCUACUCGGGAGGCCGAGGCAUGAGAAUUCCUUGAACCUGGGAGGUGGAGGUUGCAGUGAGCCAAGAUCACAUCACUGCACUCCAGCCUGGGUGAUAGAACAAGACUCCAUCUCAAAAACAAAAACCCACAAGAAUUUAUAUAUAAUUCAUUUUGGAAAUCUUUCAUCAUUAGCAAAAUUCUGUUGUAUUUCCACAAAAAUCAUGUAAUUAAUCUAGAAAAGCCUUGAACUAUGUCAUACAAUUUAUUUGGCAUGUCUUGUUUCAAUACAUCCUGCCUCUAUUUUUUUUUUUUGGAAAGUAUCUUAAAUCUAUGUCUGUUUAAUCGUAUUCAUUAGAUUAUAAGGGUUGAAUGAUUUGAGAUUUACAUGACUUAGUGACUGUCAUUUGUAUUGGUAUUAAGCCAUUUUAUGAGAGGAGGACUUUUAAGACUAUAAUGAUUAUAGACAAAUAUGUCAUCUCUAUUUAUGUCUUACUGAACAUCAGAAUGUUAAUUCUGAAAAAAAAUCAGUAAAAUACAAUGAAGAAA